AUAUCUGGUGCUCCUGAUGGGCCGGCCAGUCUGGGCCCAGCUCCCCCGAGAGGUGGUCGGAUCCUCUGGGCUGCUCGGUCGAUGCCUGUGCCACUGACGUCCAGGCAUGAGGUGGUUCCUGCCCUGGACGCUGGCAGCAGUGACAGCAGCAGCCGCCAGCACCGUCCUGGCCACGGCCCUCUCUCCAGCCCCUACGACCAUGGACUUUACCCCAGCUCCACUGGAGGACACCUCCUCACGCCCCCAAUUCUGCAAGUGGCCAUGUGAGUGCCCGCCAUCCCCACCCCGCUGCCCGCUGGGGGUCAGCCUCAUCACAGAUGGCUGUGAGUGCUGUAAGAUGUGCGCUCAGCAGCUUGGGGACAACUGCACGGAGGCUGCCAUCUGUGACCCCCACCGGGGCCUCUACUGUGACUACAGCGGGGACCGCCCGAGGUACGCAAUAGGAGUGUGUGCACAGGUGGUCGGUGUGGGCUGCGUCCUGGAUGGGGUGCGCUACAACAACGGCCAGUCCUUCCAGCCUAACUGCAAGUACAACUGCACGUGCAUCGACGGCGCGGUGGGCUGCACACCACUGUGCCUCCGAGUGCGCCCCCCGCGUCUCUGGUGCCCCCACCCGCGGCGCGUGAGCAUACCUGGCCACUGCUGUGAGCAGUGGGUAUGUGAGGACGACGCCAAGAGGCCACGCAAGACCGCACCCCGUGACACAGGAGCCUUCGAUGCUGUGGGUGAGGUGGAGGCAUGGCACAGGAACUGCAUAGCCUACACAAGCCCCUGGAGCCCUUGCUCCACCAGCUGCGGCCUGGGGGUCUCCACUCGGAUCUCCAAUGUUAACGCCCAGUGCUGGCCUGAGCAAGAGAGCCGCCUCUGCAACUUGCGGCCAUGCGAUGUGGACAUCCAUACACUCAUUAAGGCAGGGAAGAAGUGUCUGGCUGUGUACCAGCCAGAGGCAUCCAUGAACUUCACACUUGCGGGCUGCAUCAGCACACGCUCCUAUCAACCCAAGUACUGUGGAGUUUGCAUGGACAAUAGGUGCUGCAUCCCCUACAAGUCUAAGACUAUCGACGUGUCCUUCCAGUGUCCUGAUGGGCUUGGCUUCUCCCGCCAGGUCCUAUGGAUUAAUGCCUGCUUCUGUAACCUGAGCUGUAGGAAUCCCAAUGACAUCUUUGCUGACUUGGAAUCCUACCCUGACUUCUCAGAAAUUGCCAACUAGGCAGGCACAAAUCUUGGGUCUUGGGGACUAACCCAAUGCCUGUGAAGCAGUCAGCCCUUAUGGCCAAUAACUUUUCACCAAUGAGCCUUAGUUACCCUGAUCUGGACCCUUGGCCUCCAUUUCUGUCUCUAACCAUUCAAAUGACGCCUGAUGGUGCUGCUCAGGCCCAUGCUAUGAGUUUUCUCCUUGAUAUCAUUCAGCAUCUACUCUAAAGAAAAAUGCCUGUCUCUAGCUGUUCUGGACUACACCCAAGCCUGAUCCAGCCUUUCCAAGUCACUAGAAGUCCUGCUGGAUCUUGCCUAAAUCCCAAGAAAUGGAAUCAGGUAGACUUUUAAUAUCACUAAUUUCUUCUUUAGAUGCCAAACCACAAGACUCUUUGGGUCCAUUCAGAUGAAUAGAUGGAAUUUGGAACAAUAGAAUAAUCUAUUAUUUGGAGCCUGCCAAGAGGUACUGUAAUGGGUAAUUCUGACGUCAGCGCACCAAAACUAUCCUGAUUCCAAAUAUGUAUGCACCUCAAGGUCAUCAAACAUUUGCCAAGUGAGUUGAAUAGUUGCUUAAUUUUGAUUUUUAAUGGAAAGUUGUAUCCAUUAACCUGGGCAUUGUUGAGGUUAAGUUUCUCUUCACCCCUACACUGUGAAGGGUACAGAUUAGGUUUGUCCCAGUCAGAAAUAAAAUUUGAUAAACAUUCCUGUUGAUGGGAAAAGCCCCCAGUUAAUACUCCAGAGACAGGGAAAGGUCAGCCCGUUUCAGAAGGACCAAUUGACUCUCACACUGAAUCAGCUGCUGACUGGCAGGGCUUUGGGCAGUUGGCCAGGCUCUUCCUUGAAUCUUCUCCCUUGUCCUGCUUGGGGUUCAUAGGAAUUGGUAAGGCCUCUGGACUGGCCUGUCUGGCCCCUGAGAGUGGUGCCCUGGAACACUCCUCUACUCUUACAGAGCCUUGAGAGACCCAGCUGCAGACCAUGCCAGACCCACUGAAAUGACCAAGACAGGUUCAGGUAGGGGUGUGGGUCAAACCAAGAAGUGGGUGCCCUUGGUAGCAGCCUGGGGUGACCUCUAGAGCUGGAGGCUGUGGGACUCCAGGGGCCCCCGUGUUCAGGACACAUCUAUUGCAGAGACUCAUUUCACAGCCUUUCGUUCUGCUGACCAAAUGGCCAGUUUUCUGGUAGGAAGAUGGAGGUUUACCGGUUGUUUAGAAACAGAAAUAGACUUAAUAAAGGUUUAAAGCUGAAGAGGUUGAAGCUAAAAGGAAAAGGUUGUUGUUAAUGAAUAUCAGGCUAUUAUUUAUUGUAUUAGGAAAAUAUAAUAUUUACUGUUAGAAUUCUUUUAUUUAGGGCCUUUUCUGUGCCAGACAUUGCUCUCAGUGCUUUGCAUGUAUUAGCUCACUGAAUCUUCACGACAAUGUUGAGAAGUUCCCAUUAUUAUUUCUGUUCUUACAAAUGUGAAACGGAAGCUCAUAGAGGUGAGAAAACUCAACCAGAGUCACCCAGUUGGUGACUGGGAAAGUUAGGAUUCAGAUCGAAAUUGGACUGUCUUUAUAACCCAUAUUUUCCCCCUGUUUUUAGAGCUUCCAAAUGUGUCAGAAUAGGAAAACAUUGCAAUAAAUGGCUUGAUUUUUUAAUGUCAUUUUUCCCUCUUAUAGUCUUUCUAGCUCCUUUUCAAAAGACGAGAAUAUCUGAUUUUCUGAUAAUUUAGGUGCUUAAGCAUCCAAAAUACAUGGGACACACAAAAAUCCAGGAAUCCCCUGUAGCUUAUUCCCUCUUUCCCAUCGGAACCAGCUCUCAUCACACAUUUAAAAGAUGAUUCUGUUUACCCAAUGCUGCAUAUUGAAUGUUGUGUAGUUAUUCACAGGGAAUUCUGUGCAGUGUGCAGAGAGAUUCCUAAACGGGAAAAGGACUGGGAAUACAUCCUCCUUACUGUGACCUCCCCAAAACCUAGUCCAGUGCAAGGUAUACAGUGGUGCUCAUUAAAUACUUGAUGAAUACAGGAAGCUGUGCAUGUGUUCCUACUUUUAUUCGAAGCUCUCUUCUUCCAAAGCUACAUGAAAAUAGAAUUUUAACAGUCAAAAUUUUAUAUUAAGUGCCUUAGCAAAAGAGACAUUUAAUAUUUCAAAGAAAUGCAUAUGUAUGUAUACAUAUAUUUGUGUAUGCGUAUGCAAGAAUUCUUGUAUAAAGAGAAUUCACUCCAUGAAUGAUCUCUUCUGUAAGUCAGUGUGAAUCAUGUUAGAUUUUCUGAGAGUGAAAACACCUGCCAUCUACAAAUUACAAGGCUGGAUAACAGCUCACUCCAUUUGAAAUUCAGUGGAAACCCAAGAGCUAGGUUCUUACUGAAUUUGCAUCUCAAUUUGGGAAACUGAACUUAGCUUUCAAAGAUCAUAGGAAGUCUGGUUGGAGAAACUAGGGAUUAUUCUGGCAAUGGGUGCAGGAAGGUGGUCAGAAUAACCCAGUCGCCAUUGGUUUUGAGAAACGGAACUAUCUUAUGCAGAGCCCGGAGGGCAAGUCUCAGACCCAUGGGUUGAAGCCAUGGAGAAGGAAAUUUGGAUCCAAUGUAAUGAAGCGCUUUCUAAGUCAGAAUUUCCCUGCAAUGGUGUGGCCUGAUUCAAUAAAAAUUAAGAAUAAUAAAUAUAAUGGAAAAAAAUCUCCACUGAUUGAGUGUUUACUUGGUGCCAAGCACUAUGCUAAGUUGUUCAUUAUUUUAUUUAAUUGUUACAGCAAUUUUGAGUAUGCAUCUUUCACUAUUUUAUAAGUGGAAAAGAGAAGUGCCCCCAAAAAGUUAGAGCUCAAACAGCAGCUUAUUCUACCAGCCCCUGCUCUUGCGGAGGCCUCUGGAAAAGACCUGAAUGACACCUAUUGGAGAAUUACAUCUACAAGGGGCUUCAAACAGACCAAAUAGAUCAUCACCUCUGUGGUCCCUUGUUAACUAUAUGUUCUGAGACAAAGGAAAGCUACCCUAAGGGUUAGUUAACCUUUGCUGAGGAAAUUUACAUUCAUACUUAGAGUGAAUUACUCAGGUGUGCUUAGGUGUGCAAAAGGGAAGGAGACCUGAAUUCACCAAGUUAAAUCUUGCUAAACCUUAUCAUAAGCAUUUUUUGAGCGCUUAGCAUACACCAAGCCUUGUGGAAGGUGCUUUCCUGCCAUAUCUCAUUUAAUCCUCACAGCAAACCUAUAGAAUAUGGCAUUAUCAUCUGAGUCUCACAGAAGUUUAGUCGUGUACUCAAGGUCUUACCAGCUAGUGAACAGCAGACCAAGACUGGAAACCCAGGAUAGUCUGAUACCUGAGCCAUCUCUUCUUGUGCUACGCCUAGUUAUUCUGUCCCCCAAAUCAAAAGGCAUGACCUUUAUAAGAGGCGCUUUACUGACAAUAGCUGCAAUUUUAACUUUGAAAAUGAUUCAGAAUUAUCAAAGAUAGUAGAUUCGAAUGACAUGAUUGUCUAUAAUCUCGCUAGCCUUGUACUGUGUGUGCAUAGCAAUUACAGGGAAGUAAUCUAGCUCCUGACUAUUAUGUUGAACUAUGUCGCUGCUUUUUACAAACUUGUCUUGAUCCAAAGCAGUCACAAUGAUAACCCUGCAUAUCUGGGAAUCAUAAGUCAACUAUGUAUCCCUGUGUGUGUAUAUAUAUGUAUGUAUGUAUCUAUUUUCAAACUGUGAUUUAAUAUUUAAAUAUUCCUACUGCCAUUUUUGUGACUGAAAAACUACACAUGAGGAAACGUCUUAGAAUUUUCCAAUAGAGGAAAAAUAACACUUGGGCAAUCUGUCAUGUUUCACAACAGUUCUCAUUUUUCUCAUGAUUUGUGUAGCGUGGAAUGUGUUUGCUCAAUGUGAAGGGUUUUCAUUGCUCAAUUUCUCUGUGUAAGUCUUUUCCUUAAGGUAAUAAACCAUCAGCAAAGUCACAUACUGGAGUUGGUGGCUUUUCUUGUACAGGCAGUUGUUAUGAGACAAUGAUGGAGCAUUGAGCAUGUUCAAUAAAUGUGCAGAUGGUGGAAA